GCCACUCCCGCUCUCUCAGCGCCGCCGUCGCCACCGCCACCGCCACCGCCACUACCACCGUCUGAGUCUGCAGUCCCGAGAUCCCAGCCAUCAUGUCCAUAGAGAAGAUCUGGGCCCGGGAGAUCCUGGACUCCCGCGGGAACCCCACAGUGGAGGUGGAUCUCUAUACUGCCAAAGGUCUUUUCCGGGCUGCAGUGCCCAGUGGAGCCUCUACGGGCAUCUAUGAGGCCCUGGAGCUGAGGGAUGGAGACAAACAGCGUUACUUAGGCAAAGGUGUCCUGAAGGCAGUGGACCACAUCAACUCCACCAUCGCGCCAGCCCUCAUCAGCUCAGGUCUCUCUGUGGUGGAGCAAGAGAAACUGGACAACCUGAUGCUGGAGUUGGAUGGGACUGAGAACAAAUCCAAGUUUGGGGCCAAUGCCAUCCUGGGUGUGUCUCUGGCCGUGUGUAAGGCAGGGGCAGCUGAGCGGGAACUGCCCCUGUAUCGCCACAUUGCUCAGCUGGCCGGGAACUCAGACCUCAUCCUGCCUGUGCCGGCCUUCAACGUGAUCAAUGGUGGCUCUCAUGCUGGCAACAAGCUGGCCAUGCAGGAGUUCAUGAUCCUCCCAGUGGGAGCUGAGAGCUUUCGGGAUGCCAUGCGACUAGGUGCAGAGGUCUACCAUACACUCAAGGGAGUCAUCAAGGACAAAUACGGCAAGGAUGCCACCAAUGUGGGGGAUGAAGGUGGCUUUGCCCCCAAUAUCCUGGAGAACAGUGAAGCCUUGGAGCUGGUGAAGGAAGCCAUCGACAAGGCUGGCUACACGGAAAAGAUCGUUAUUGGCAUGGAUGUUGCUGCCUCAGAGUUUUAUCGUGAUGGCAAAUAUGACUUGGACUUCAAGUCUCCCACUGAUCCUUCCCGAUACAUCACUGGGGACCAGCUGGGGGCACUCUACCAGGACUUUGUCAGGGACUAUCCUGUGGUCUCCAUUGAGGACCCAUUUGACCAGGAUGAUUGGGCUGCCUGGUCCAAGUUCACAGCCAAUGUAGGGAUCCAGAUUGUGGGUGAUGACCUGACAGUGACCAACCCAAAACGUAUUGAGCGGGCAGUGGAAGAAAAGGCCUGCAACUGUCUGCUGCUCAAGGUCAACCAGAUCGGCUCGGUCACUGAAGCCAUCCAAGCGUGCAAGCUGGCCCAGGAGAAUGGCUGGGGGGUCAUGGUGAGUCAUCGCUCAGGAGAGACUGAGGACACAUUCAUUGCUGACCUGGUGGUGGGGCUGUGCACAGGCCAGAUCAAGACUGGUGCCCCGUGCCGUUCUGAACGUCUGGCUAAAUACAACCAGCUCAUGAGAAUUGAGGAAGAGCUGGGGGAUGAAGCUCGCUUUGCCGGACAUAACUUCCGUAAUCCCAGUGUGCUGUGAUUCCUCUGCUUGCCUGGAGACGUGGAACCUCUGUCUCAUCCUCCUGGAACCUUGCUGUCCUGAUCUGUGAUAGUUCACCCCCUGAGAUCCCCUGAGCCCCAGGGUGCCCAGAACUUCCCUGAUUGACCUGCUCCGCUGCUCCUUGGCUUACCUGACCUCUUGCUGUCUCUGCUCGCCCUCCUUUCUGUGCCCUACUCAUUGGGGUUCCGCACUUUCCACUUCUUCCUUUCUCUUUCUCUCUUCCCUCAGAAACUAGAAAUGUGAAUGAGGAUUAUUAUAAAAGGGGGUCCGUGGAAGAAUGAUCAGCAUCUGUGAUGGGAGCGUCAGGGUUGGUGUGCUGAGGUGUUAGAGAGGGACCAUGUGUCACUUGUGCUUUGCUCUUGUCCCACGUGUCUUCCACUUUGCAUAUGAGCCGUGAACUGUGCAUAGUGCUGGGAUGGAGGGGAGUGUUGGGCAUGUGAUCACGCCUGGCUAAUAAGGCUUUAGUGUAUUUAUUUAUUUAUUUAUUUUAUUUGUUUUUCAUUCAUCCCAUUAAUCAUUUCCCCAUAACUCAAUGGCCUAAAACUGGCCUGACUUGGGGGAACGAUGUGUCUGUAUUUCAUGUGGCUGUAGAUCCCAAGAUGACUGGGGUGGGAGGUCUUGCUAGAAUGGGAAGGGUCAUAGAAAGGGCCUUGACAUCAGUUCCUUUGUGUGUACUCACUGAAGCCUGCGUUGGUCCAGAGCGGAGGCUGUGUGCCUGGGGGAGUUUUCCUCUAUACAUCUCUCCCCAACCCUAGGUUCCCUGUUCUUCCUCCAGCUGCACCAGAGCAACCUCUCACUCCCCAUGCCACGUUCCACAGUUGCCACCACCUCUGUGGCAUUGAAAUGAGCACCUCCAUUAAAGUCUGAAUCAGUGCA